AGAGCCGGAGCCGUGGCCUGCGGGGCCGGCGACAUGGAUCCCCUGUUCCAGCAAACGCACAAGCAGGUCCACGAGAUCCAGUCUUGCAUGGGACGCCUGGAGACGGCAGACAAGCAGUCUGUGCACAUAGUAGAAAACGAAAUCCAAGCAAGCAUAGACCAGAUAUUCAGCCGUCUAGAACGUCUGGAGAUUUUGUCCAGCAAGGAGCCCCCUAACAAAAGGCAAAAUGCCAGACUUCGGGUUGACCAGUUAAAGUAUGAUGUCCAGCACCUGCAGACUGCGCUCAGAAACUUCCAGCAUCGGCGCCAUGCAAGGGAGCAGCAGGAGAGACAGCGAGAAGAGCUUCUGUCUCGAACCUUCACCACUAACGACUCUGACACCACCAUACCAAUGGACGAAUCACUGCAGUUUAACUCCUCCCUCCAGAAAGUUCACAACGGCAUGGAUGACCUCAUUUUAGAUGGGCACAAUAUUUUAGAUGGACUGAGGACCCAGAGACUGACCUUGAAGGGGACUCAGAAGAAGAUCCUUGACAUUGCCAACAUGCUGGGCUUGUCCAACACAGUGAUGCGGCUCAUCGAGAAGCGGGCUUUCCAGGACAAGUACUUUAUGAUAGAGCCCCCCAAAUUCUUAUCUCAACAAGAGUCAAAUAAAGACUUGAAAAGACUUGACAUCUAAACUACACUUAUUAAGGAAAAACUCAUUAAUUCCCUAUGGAGAUCUGAGGCCAAGCACACCUCUGAAGCAGUGCAUGGCUUGGAAUCCUGUCUGCUCUUCACCGAACCAUUCCUUCUGCACUCACCUCCUCCAGAAAGCCUUCCAAACCAGGUCUUAACUCCAUCAUCCUAACUACCUUGUCAGCACUCACUUUUGUUAACACUUUGAUUCAGCAGUACUUGGGUUCCAUGAGUAUUUGAGCAUAGUUGUGUGUGUGUCUCAUCUCUCUCACCCCAAACCCACUCCACCCCACCCUACCCUACCAACUGACUCUCCUGAACUCUCUAGAGCAAGAGCUGUGUCUCCAUCAGACUAGCAACUUCCUGAGGGCGAAGACUCUAAUUCCUUAUCCCAUUGGGAUCCAGAUGCUGUCUCUCCUCACAUCAGACUGGGAAUGGAAAAUCUUUCCAUGCCCCAUGGAGCCUCCUUGGCAAGACAGGAAGAUACGGAGUCUGAACCCCAUAGAGAUGGAGAGUGGGAGGAAGAAGGUAGCCGGGAGCAGUUAGCAGGAGGGUCCAUCUUAACCUUCAGGGAAAAACCGAUUCACAGCACAUAAAGCUAGUUCUGGAUCAGAAUCUGUUAUUCAACAACACUUGCAAGGGUUUAACUCAGAUCCUGUCCCCUCUGGGGUAGAAAUCUCUACCCGCCUAAGGCCAGGAUUCUGCCUUGCCAGUCCUUUUUUUUUUUUUUUUUUUUUUUUUUUUUUGAGACAGAGUUUCGCUUUUGUUGCCCAGGCUGGAGUGCAAUGCUGCCAUCUUAGCUCACUGCAACCUCCACCUCCCGGGUUCAAGCGAUUCUCCUGCCUCAGCCUCCCGAGUAGCUGGGAUUACAGGCAUGCACCACCAUGCCUGGCUAAAUUUUUUUGUAUUUUCUUAGUAGAGGCAGGGUUUCUGUCUCUACUGGUUGGCCAGGCUAGUCUCAAACUCCUGACCUCAGGUGAUCCACCCACCUUGGCCUACCAAAGUGCUGGGAUUACAGGCGUGAGCCACCGCACCCAGCCCUUGCCAGUGUUUCUUAUUUCUCUUGUCCCUUGAUGAUUGUGUAAUGAUGAAUCCCUUCGUUAGGAAGCUUGUCAAAUGCAAGUAGACGCUGAGGGGGCGGCCAUGUGUCUACUGUCUCGUGGCUCCUGUUGGAUGGGAGUAGCCUGCGUGGCUGCCAGUGCUGGCUGGAGAGGAUACCACCAUCUGCUCUCGUCAGCAUGCUGCCCUGCCUUUGAGUCCCCUCACUCCCGCCCCAAGACUAAAUCCUUGAAAGAGCAGCUCCACAGCGAGCAUGUGGCAAGAAAGGAUGCUAAUGGAGGGAAGAAAGUGAUGAAUCCCCAAAAGAGUCAGGGAAAGCCACACAAGAAGGAAAAAUAGCUGCAUAAAGGUUGCGGGGGUGAGCUGGGCGAGGCUGCCCGCUGACAGGUGAAUCAAGACUCCAGAGAGCUGGGUACGGUGGCUCACACUUGUAGUCCCAGCACUUUGGGAGGCCCAGGCGGGUGGAUCGUGUGAACCCAGGAGUUCAAAACCAUCCUGGGUGACAUGGUGAAACCCCGUCUCUACAAAAAAUACAAAAAUUAGGCACAGUGGCAUGUGCCUGUAGUCUCAGCUACUUUGGAGGCUGAGGUGGGAGGACUGCUUGAGCCCAGGAGGUGGAGGUUGCAGUGAGCUGAGUUUACAUCACUGUACACCAGCCUGGGCAACAGAGUGAGACCCUGCCUCAAAAAGAAAACAAAAAAAGAAACCCAGGCUAAGCGCUGUGGCUCACGCCUGUAUUCCCAGCAAUUUGGGAGGCUGAGGCAGGUGGAUCACUUGAGGUCAGGAGUCUGAGACCAGCCUGGCCAACAUGGUGAAACCCCAUCUCUACUAAAAAUACAAAAACUAGCCAGGUGUGGUGGUGGGUGCCUGUAGUCCCAGCUACACAGGAGGCUGAGGCAGGAGAAUUGCUUGAACCUGGGAGGCAGAGGUUGCAGUGAGCUGAGAUCAUGCCACUGCACUCCAGCCUAGGUGACAGAGUGAGACUUGGUCUCAAAACAAACAAACAAACAAACAAACAAAACCCAGACAGCAGGAAGCCCAGGUGAGGAGAAGGGGAGAGGCAAACAGGACAUGAAGGAAGAUUUGUUUGGUAGAGAGAAGGGAAUUGAUGGCAGCCCCAGGAUGCAGUUUGAACCUGUAUUUGGUAGAAGCAGCGAUGGGGAAAUGGGCCAGAUAUCGGACAGGAGAGAGACAUGAUACAAUCAGUGCUAAUGAUCCAGACAUCUCCAUGGAGGAGGAUGAGCACUCAGGGGAAACGGAGGCAAGGCACUCACCCAGGACGCUGCAGCAGGGAUCAGUGUGCCUAGCAUGGCAAUGGAAGUGAGAGGGAGUCGGAGAUCUGACUGAGCGACUCCUAACUUUGAGAGUUGGUGGCUCAUUCCCACCAAGGGGCUUAUGGCUGCUGCUUUGGGAGUCUUUGCUGCCAAAUGUCACUGGCCGGGGGUCACCUCACCCGUAACCCAUGGAGAGUGGGUCUCCUCUCCCCAUUUGUGCAGGACUUUCUUUCCAUUGGCAGCAACUGGCCAGGGGGCCUCAGAGGAGCUGGGAAUGGGGAGCAGGCUGCCAAGAAGGUUUGGUCAGGCCAACCAACUUGGAGGGCAGGGAAAGAAGUGGAGCCGUCAACCUUCACAUUUUACAGGCAUACAAAUCACACACCAAAUAAGGAGAAAUAUGGGACACAUUUGCACAAUAAUUCAAGACAGGAUCUCCAUGGCAACAAUUACCCAAAAAUCCACUCCUGACAGUUGCAACAGCGGGAGCUAGCAAAGAAGACUGGGGGUGGGAAACGUGUGUGGGGGCUCAGAGAAUGGCUUCCUUUUAUUCUCGAACUGAAGGAAGUGCUGACGGCAGGAAGCAAGGUGUCUCACAGCCUGACUAAGCCAAGAGCCACUGGAAGUAGGAUCUGGAAGAAGCCUUAGAGACGUCUGUGUGAGCUCCUUUUGAGCUGCUUAGAGGCCUGGGUGUGGGAUACCACAGUGAGAUGUGCCAGUGGGAUGUGCCAGCUCAGGGGAGGGGGCCAUCAGGGCAUCGCCCUCCCACCACUCCCUCUGAUGGACAAGAGUUCUCCCUAGCCUCCAGAGGUCCUCACAGGGGCACAGUGAGAGAUGGAGCCAACUUCCGGCGAAGUCAAAGGUUCUGGGACAUUUAAGUCUGCCUGAAAACUGAGUCCAGUCCAUAGAAAGCUGACACAUGACAUAGGUUAGGAGAACGGAGCUCUAGCCUGCUCUGCUCCCCUCCCAGACUUGCUGUGUGGCCCCUCAGUUUCCUCUACAGUGAAAUGUACAACCUACCUCCAAGAACUAUUACAAGGCUGAGUGAAUAGCAUGAGAUGGGAAAUGCUUUUACCAAAAUCACUGCCAAUGCAAAAAUAAGAGGUUUCUGUGCAGCCAUGAAGAGUGGCCUGAGAAAGAUAGCUGCAUGCAAGGCUGUCCUUAACAGGCAGAGGAGUUUCCUAGGUCAGGUGAGAGUCAGUACAAAGACUGUGGUGGGAAUCUAGAAUGUGGCUAGGCAGCGAUACUGAUGAGAUGGUGGGAAGUAGGAGGUUGGGCGUAGUGGCAGAAGUGUCACCUGUGUCCUACCACCAGACAGAUGGACAGACUGACUGUGAGCUCAGAGCAGGCAGUAGAGUGUGUAACCUCCAAUUUACAAACAUUUUUAAUCACACACCAAAAAGGAAAAGCAUUCUGCUUUCUUUUUGGAGUAACAUAAAUCCAACCCCGUUCCCCACCCACAUCCUUUUAAGUGUAUUUCUUUUUGUCUGGUAGUCCUCAAAAGCCAUUGGCUAUUUUUCAGAUCCUAGAGCUCAGAUUGCCUUAAAUCGCUUGAGAAAGGAGAGUUUUUUCAUCUUUCUUUUUGGAACUAAGACUUUAGAGCAAAGGAAAAGGUUCUUCUGGGUUUCAUUUGCAUUUGGAAGCCCAGGUUUUUGGGAAAAAAACACUCUCAAGAGCUUAUUACUAUUAUAAAUGUUUAGCCAUGUGAUUUUUCCUCAAGAGGGCACCCAAAACUUUUCAUACCAACUCCCAUGGAUAGCAGUCCCCUUAUGCUGAAUUAUGGUGGGAAAGGAUUAAGGUAGGACAUUUCUUGAGCAUUUUUUUCCUAUUCUGGGCUCUCUCCUUUGCCAUCCCACUCUCCACUACAAAACUUUUCCCUUCCCUUUUGUCUCACUAACCAUGGAAAGUCCUCCAAUCCUUGGAGGUCCUCAGAAGCCAUUCUUCCCACCACUGGAGCUGACUUUCUUCCCUCUCCUGGACUGAGCAGGAAGACCGAUUCAUGAGAGAGCUCCUCUAAAGGAAUUCAGGCUGGGCCCUGAGACAGGACAUCAUGGAGUGGACUUUGGAGUGGCCACAAUAGUCCAGAUCUGGUCCUCAGCAGUAGAGUCCAGAAACUUGGUUGGGCCAGGACAUCCAAAAGUUGUCAGCCUCUCAGGACUGAUUCAGGCUAACCAAAUUCAUUGAUGGGCAACCAGAAUGCCAUUUCCUGAAUAAUAUAUCUACCAAAAGACUGGUAUCCAAAAUAUGGAAAGAGCUCUCAAAGCUCAACAAUAAGAAAACAAGCAACCCAACUUUUAAAAAGCAAAAGACACUUUACUAAAGAAGAUAUACAGAUGGCACUUAAGAACAUGAAAAGAUGCUCAACAUCAUCAUUCAAUAGAAGACAAAUUAGACACACAAUGAGGUGUCACUACACACUUGGCAUACAUACAAACAAACACAACACAAAAUCUGACAAUAUCAAGUGCUGACGAGGACAUAGAGCACCUAGAAUGCUCACACAUUGCUGGUGGAAAUGCAAAAUGGAACAGCCACUAUGAAAAACAGUUUGGCAGUGUCUUACAGAGCUAAGCGUGUGCUUCCUAUAUGACCCAGCAAUCUCAUUUCUAGGUAUUUACCCAAGUGAAAGGAAAACUUUUGUUCACACAUACAUAAAAAAACUCUACAUGAGGAUUUAUUUGCAAUCACCAAAACAGGAUACAACCCAAAUAUCCUUCAACUGAAGACAGAUAAAAAUUUAAAUUUAAAAACCUGUGAUACAUCCAUCCAAUGGAAUAUUACUACUAAGCAAGAAAAAGGAACGAACUACUGAAGUGUGAAACGAUAUGGAUGCAUUAAGAUAAGUGUGAGAAGCCAGAUGGAAAAGGCAGCUUAUUGGGUGAUUCCAUUUAUUUGAAAUUCAGGAAAAGAAAAACCACAGGGACAAAGAACAGAUCAGUAGUUGUCUGCAUUAAGGGAAGAAGAGUUUGUGGAUUUGGCUACAAAGUGGCAGCAUGAAGGAGUAUCUCGAUUGUGUUCAUGAUGACACAACUCUAAGUAUUUGUCAAAAUAUAUAGUGCUCUACGUCAAAAAAGUAAAUUUUACCCUAAAUUUGAAAUAAAAAUAAAAGGCAUUUAUAAUGA